GUCCCGGCAACGCGCGGCGGCUCAGCGGCCUGGCAGAGGUGAGUGGCCUUAGGGCUAGGGCGGCCGACCCAGGUCCUUAGGAGCCAGGCCGGGGUUUGGGGCCGAGGAUGUGACCGGUGGCGGGCGUCGGGACCCUCCCGUCUCCUCCCACGAUCCCGGCGCCGCCGAGUCCCCGCGGCCCCUCGCGAGUCCCAUCGAGGCUGGGGCGGGCUUGGCGCGGGGUCCAGGUCGCUCGUCGGACUAUGGCUGUCGCCCCCGCCCGGCCUCGAAUCGCGGCUGAUUCCGGUAGCUGGGAGAGUCCCUUUGGAAUGGGCGGGGUGGGGAGGUGGGCGGCGCCAUCACACCCCCGAGGCGAAACGGGACAAACGAGAGAUGCAAAACAAAAACAUGCUAUGUUUGGUCACUCGCUGGGUCGGCCCUGAGGGUCGUGUUGCAUCAAACCGCCAGCGCAUGGCUUCUCAGUACCGUCCGCUGGAUGCAGCGAGGACCCUGCGCAGGCCGAAGGCUCUGGACUGUGGCCUGGAGGGCGAGGCUUUGUAGGGUGGCCCCGGGUGCCUGUCCCCGAGAGUCCACCGUGGAGCCCCAUCCCGGAGUUCCCUACUCAGCGUCACCGAGGAAGGCUACUCAAAGCCCUGUGACCCCGUGCCGCUUAGCUGAAUGGGCUUAACAGAUUCUUUCCCAAAAGCUGGUUUGAUGGAGGCACUUGUAGAGGCUCUGGAGACGCUGGACGCCUGAAAGUGAGAGGAGUACUUCGGUUAGAAUAAAUACAGUUUUUCUCCUGUUCCCCAAAGUUGAUGUAUUUCCCGGUUUUAUGUUCCAGAGACUGGAACUUUGUUUCAAGAAAAGGAAAGGUACUUGUUUCCGACCUGAAGCUAUUACAGAUUGUCAUCAAGUACAUAACUAUUUUAUUGUCAGCCAUCUCUCCUCCUUGUGUUAACUUUUUAAAUUAUACUGAUAAUACUCAUUUUGGGAACUUGUUAAGAGGCCGUUGAAAGGAACUAUGAACAAUUAUAUUAAUGCAUUGUGUAUGGAACUCAUUCAGGCAGGCCUGGAACCCGUUUCUUAUAUUGAUACAACAGGAAGAAUCUCUCUCCUUGCUAAGUUUCAUCCGCGCAGGGCCUGUUCUGUGCAAGGCACUGUUGUAAGGAGGUGGGAAUACUGGGUGCCUCCUGCUCUCUGGGGAAGAUAAUAUGGGGGGCAAUGUGUGAGCAGUGAAACUCACAUUUACGGUAAAGUCUAAAUGCAGCCACGGAGAAGCGCAACGUUGUGUGGGGACACUGGGCAAGAAGCACACGACAAAGGUUUCAGCGCUGAGGAGGCCUGAGUUCCGUCAUGGCCCUCUAUUAUGACCACCAGAUAGAAGCCCCGGAUGCAGCAGGGUCACCCUCAUUUAUCAGCUGGCACCCUGUCCAUCCAUUCUUGGCAGUUGCUUACAUCAGCACAACCUCAACAGGCAGCGUGGAUAUUUACCUGGAGCAAGGGGAGUGCGUGCCAGAUACACACGUCGAGAGGCCGUUCCGGGUUGCUUCCCUGUGCUGGCACCCGACGCGGCUGGUGCUGGCUGUGGGCUGGGAGACUGGAGAAGUGACGGUGUUUAACAAGCAGGACAAGGAGCAGCACACGAUGCCCCUGACACACACAGCCGACAUCACCGUGCUCCGUUGGAGCCCCAGUGGAAACUGCCUGCUGUCUGGGGACAGGCUUGGUGUCUUGCUCUUGUGGAGGUUGGACCAAAGGGGCCGAGUGCAAGGGACGCCUCUGCUGAAACACGAGUAUGGGAAACACCUCACGCACUGCAUCUUCCGGCUCCCCCCUCCUGGCGAGGACCUGGUUCAGUUGGCAAAGGCAGCUGUGAGCGGUGAUGAGAAAGCCCUGGACAUGUUUAACUGGAAGAAGAGCAGUUCUGGAAGUUUGCUGAAGAUGGGGUCUCACGAGGGGCUGUUGUUCUUUGUCAGUCUGAUGGACGGGACAGUGCACUAUGUGGAUGAGAAGGGCAAGACCACUCAGGUGGUGUCCGCAGACAGCACGAUUCAGAUGCUGUUCUACAUGGAGAAGAGGGAGGCACUGGUGGUGGUCACAGAGAACCUCCGGCUGUCCCUGUACACGGUGCCUCCUGAGGGCAAAGCAGAAGAAGUGAUGAAGGUCAAGCUGAGCGGGAAAACCGGCCGCCGGGCAGACAUCGCUUUGAUUGAAGGCAGCCUUCUCGUGAUGGCCGUCGGGGAGGCUGCCCUCAGAUUCUGGGACAUAGAACGAGGAGAGAAUUAUAUACUGAGUCCAGAUGAGAAGUUUGGCUUUGAGAAAGGAGAGAAUAUGAACUGUGUGUGUUACUGUAAAGUCAAAGGUCUUCUGGCCGCUGGUACCGACAGAGGGCGAGUAGCCAUGUGGAGGAAAGUACCAGACUUCCUGGGCAGCCCCGGGGCAGAGGGCAAGGACAGGUGGGCCCUUCAGACCCCUACCGAGCUCCAAGGAAACAUCACGCAAAUCCAGUGGGGUUCCAGGAAGAACCUGCUGGCAGUGAACAGCGUCAUCUCCGUGGCCAUCCUCAGCGAGCGGGCCAUGUCGUCACACUUCCACCAGCAAGUGGCCGCCAUGCAGGUCUCCCCGAGUCUGCUGAAUGUGUGCUUCCUGUCCACGGGGGUCGCACACAGCCUGCGCACCGACAUGCACAUCAGUGGAGUGUUUGCCACCAAGGAUGCUGUCGCAGUCUGGAACGGAAGGCAGGUGGCGAUCUUCGAGCUUUCUGGAGCCGCGAUACGGAGUGCAGGGACCUUCUUGUGUGAGACGCCUGUGUUAGCAAUGCAUGAAGAAAACGUUUACACGGUGGAGUCAAACCGAGUUCAAGUUCGAACCUGGCAGGGGACUGUCAAACAACUCCUCCUUUUCUCGGAGACUGAGGGGAAUCCCUGCUUCUUGGACAUCUGUGGGAAUUUCCUGGUUGUAGGGACAGACUUGGCUCACUUUAAAAGCUUUGAUCUUUCCCGAAGAGAGGCCAAAGCACACUGUAGCUGCAGGAGCCUGGCGGAGCUGGUCCCUGGGGUGGGGGGCAUCGCUUCUCUGCGGUGCAGCAGCAGCGGGAGCACCAUCAGCAUCCUCCCCAGCAAGGCUGACAACAGCCCUGAUUCCAAAAUCUGCUUCUACGAUGUUGAAAUGGACACAGUGACCGUCUUUGACUUCAAGACUGGACAAAUUGAUCGGAGAGAGACGCUGUCCUUUAAUGAGCAAGAGACUAAUAAGAGCCACCUCUUUGUGGAUGAGGGACUGAAAAAUUAUGUUCCCGUGAACCACUUCUGGGACCAGAGUGAGCCCCGGCUGUUUGUAUGCGAAGCCGUGCAGGAGACGCCGCGCUCCCAGCCUCAGUCUGCAAACGGGCAGCCCCAAGAUGGGCGCGCUGGCCCUGCGGCAGAUGUUUUGAUCCUGUCCUUCUUCAUUUCCGAAGAGCACGGCUUCCUGCUUCAUGAGAGCUUCCCCCGGCCUGCCACCUCCCACAGUCUCCUGGGGAUGGAAGUGCCUUAUUACUACUUCACAAGAAAGCCCGAAGAAGCAGACAGAGAAGACGAGGUGGAGCCUGGGUGCCACCACAUCCCUCAGAUGGUGUCCAGGAGACCCCUGCGAGACUUUGUGGGGCUGGAGGACUGCGACAAGGCCACCCGGGACGCCAUGCUCCACUUCAGCUUCUUUGUCACCAUAGGAGACAUGGACGAAGCCUUCAAAUCCAUCAAGCUCAUCAAAAGGGCACUCUUCAGGUAACUGAUGCAGGAAUCUAAGAGGGAAGCAGCCUCACCACUCAGGAGCGGGUCCCCGCGCCCGCAUCCAUCACAGACACCAGAAUCCAGGCUCAGGAGCAGGUCCCUGUGCCCGCAUUCAUCACAGACACCAGAAUCCAGGGAGCAGCAGAAUGUCCCAAGAGCCCUGAAGGUGCUGGCCUCUAGGGUGACUGCUGUGUGUCCUGGGUGGAGGCCGAGAGGGGAUGGGGAGAUCCUCAAGCUGCCUCCUCAGAGCACGCCUGUGGGAAGCCAGCCCAGCAGGGGAAGCUGUCGAGGUUCACGCGUGCACGGGGCAGGCACGCUGGCAUCAAGGCUCAGGGGUGGUGGGGGAUGCGGGCUGCUUUACUUCGUGAGUGUUUACGUGGUUAGAAGUAUCCGUUGGAACCACUAUUGCCAGUAUUAGCAAUUCCACACGGUUCAACCUCAACAUUUAUUGAAAUGCAAUCUGGAUUCACAGAAUAACCUCAAAGCUCUGGAGCCGAGGCAUCUGCUUCCCACCUGGCCCUUGGGCUGGGUGCUGCUCCAGCGCUCACAUCUGCCCCGGCCCCAGGCUGAGGUGGUGUGUGGGAUCGUCUCAGUCUAGGCUUUCGGCGUCCCAGCAUCCCUGGAGGCACACUGCUCCUCGCCACUGAGGGUCCCCCCGCCGUCCUACCCACUGUAUUUCAAGCUGCUUCCCUCCACAGCGUCCCCUCCUGUCACUCGGGGCGGAGGGAGCUCUCCUUCCUGGAUGCCAGGCUUUUCCACUGUGCCCGCUCCGGCCUGGGUGGCGCCCCCAGCCCUGAGACCUCCAGGGUGUGAGGGCAGUGCGCAGAGAGUGGAGGCAUGAAGGACCCUGGGGCACGGGGUCCCCGGGCUGCUGAGGAGUCUGAGCAGCCAGCACAUGGCACCAUGAGCCUUCCGCUGGCAAGGGGGAGAGCGGAGCACGCUGCCUGCCCGCAGACAGGCAGGCACCACUGACAGGGCCAUGGGAAGCGGCAGCAGCUGCCCCUCGCUCAUUUUUCUCGCAGCAAAACAGACACCCCAGUGAGCGUCACUGCCACGUAACUGAGAGCUCACGUUCCUUCAUCUCCAAAGUAACUGCAGAGUUAGAAACCAUAGCGCUCCCGCGAGGUUCUCUCUAAAGAAGGAACAGAAGACGCGGGGGCUGAGAGCCAGCCUGGUGGCCAAGGGGUUCCCGUACGGACAGCGGGAAAGCCUGGCAGCAGGUGAGGACCUGGCUCAGCAUGGGCAUAGGUGGCCGUGGGGCCAGAGUGCUUGGAGGAAGGGGCAGAGCCCAGGGCACUGGAAAUGCCAGAGGACAGCAGAGAUGUGCUUGACCUCAGCCUGGCACCGUGCAACUUGCUGAGGCCUAAGGCGUGGGGCGGCAUUUGCACCAUGUGGCUUGCUGAGGCCCAAGGCAUGGGACGUCACUGGCACUGUGCGGCUUGGUGAGGCCCAAGGUGUGGGGUGGCUUGGCACCGUGUGGCUUGGUGAGUCCUGAGGCUUGGGUCGGCGUUGGCACCGUGUGGCUUGGUGAGGCCCAAGGCGUGGGGCGGCGUGGCACUGUGCAGCUUGGUGAGGCCUGAGGCGUGGGGCCGUCUGGCACUCUGCAGCUUGCUGAGGCCUGAGGUGGGGGGCCAUCUGGCACUGUGCAGCUUGCUGAGGCCUGAGGCGUGGGGCCAUCUGGCACUGUGCAGCUUGCUGAGGCCUGAGGUGGGGGGCCGCGUGGCACCGUGCAGCUUGGUGAGGCCUGAGGUAGGGGGCGCUUUUGCCCUGGGUUUCUCACCUGCCCUAGGGCCUGUGCAGAUGGGACCAGCAGGAGCCAGGGUUGAGGCAGACACUGCCCUGGCUGACUGGCAGGACCUUCCUGACUGCUCCAACGGACUCCACAGCCAGCCCCAAGCAGUGACCACGUACAGCCUGCAGGGACCGGAGUGAGGCCUGCAUUUUGAGGGCGUCCUGUCCACACAUUAGGGACGUGUGUGAGCUCUGGAGGCCCCUUCCAGCAGGAUCUGUGGCACGGUGCUGUGCCAUCUUUGCUCUUAACUGUCUUGGCAAUGACUUCCAUUCAGAAGCCUCUGCUUCUCUAAACAUUGCAAAAUGAGGGAGGCAUUAAAACAUCACGCAGAAGGUCAUGUUCGAGAGAGGAGCAGCUCAGAUUCCCUGCCCAGGGCUCUGCGCUCUGCCCUGGAGGGGAGGAAAGACCAGAAUGAAGGGGGAGGAGGGAUGCAGAGCUGCCCUGGGAGGAGCAUAGCCCAGAAUGGCAUGACCGAGGUGGGCUUGAGCACCAGGCACAGCUGCACGUGUAGUUGUGGUGAGGGUGAGUGACCAAGGUUCCUGGGAGCUGGGAAUAAGCAGACGCACCCCUGACCUGUCCUCUCGCCCUCAGCCCUGGCCUCUCAGCCUUCCUUCCUCGCAGCUCCAGGCACACAGCCCUGUGCCACACACCAUGGCAGGGGCUCUGUGCAGCAGCCGUGCCCCACAAGCCACUCUGCAGCCUCCAAGUCCCCAGGGUGCAUGGCUCACCACAAGGGCACCCACAGACCCACCGCCCUGCCAGGAAGGAGGCACUCCUGCCCGAGCCUUCCUGUCUGAGCCACGCUCCCGCCUGCCCCAAGAAAGCUGUUUGGAGCUGGCGUUCACUGCUUGGGUGUUAUACGGGUUCCUGGGGUGCUGCCUGUGUGCGUGGCUCUGCGUGGCUCUGCGUGGCUGUGCGUGGUAGCAGCUGACUUUUAAAGGUGUCGGUGAGAACGUGGUUCAGCUGGGUCCUGGCCGAGCAGGGGGUGAAGCCCGGGAGCUCUGUCCUCCACCUGUAUUCAGGCAGGGUCUUACGUGCCCGUUUGAUGUGUGGCGGGGCAUGCGUGGUGACGGAGCCACGUGGAGCCACCGGAGAGAGGGGUGGGGCUCCCCCUCAGCUAGCGCCAGGCUCUGGCUCGCCUGCCUCGAGAUUCAAUCACACGGUCAUCUGUUCCCAAGCCACCUUGUUUCAGAUGCCUGACAGAACGCACGAAAUACAGAGAGAUGACGUAAAUAUCCAAAACGAGACGAAGUGAGGAGGAGAAAUUGAGACCCCCUCUGGACAUGGCAUGUGAGGUGGACCUCAGGCCUCCCUGGUCCCCCGAGCUCCUCACAGGGAAAGAGCACCCCUGAUCCGUAAUGAAAGUCCCACUCACCACAGGCCACAGGACACCCCUGGCAGGGGCACGGGAGGGCCUGAACCUGGAUGAAGUCGAGACCGGGCUCCUCUGCCCUGGGUCCAGCCCUCUUUGCCCUGACCAGAGUUCAGGAUGUCCGGGGCGCGUCCCCUGUCCCUCAGGCAGGCUCCUGGUGAUGUUUGCGAGUGACGAGCGCUGGAUGAUUUUGACUCCAUGUGCCCCAUGGGGCAGGGCCUCAGGGCACAGAGCCGUCCGGAGACAUCCACGCGGGCCUCAGCGACAUCCGGAAACCCCGAGGGUGGCCUGGUGUGCGUGAGGAGGCACGCGGUGUGGCGUUGUCUUCCCUGGCCUGCGUGAGGAGGCACGCGGUGUGACGUUGUCUUCCCUGGCUUGCCCCACCCCGACCCUAGACUGGUUCUCGGGAUGGAAUUGUGAGCAAACCAGCACCCAGCCUCACAGCACAGACGGUCGCAGCCCAUCAUACGUGCUGGGUGAUUUUACAAGGAACACUGGCCAAGGCAGGAAGGAAGACGCUAGGAGCUGGCUGGACUCAGUGGGGUGGCCAGGCUAGAGCUGCUGCCCCCAGCCAGGGCUGACUCCCAGGCCUGCCUAGGUCACACGGCAGGAUUUUGCAGAAAGGUUCAUAGGCUAGCUUGAUGUGCAGUGGUGGCAGGUAGCAGCCCCUCACCCGAUUGGGGACAUGGGUGCACGUGAGUGGGGGCAGCGAAUGUUGCUGUGGACAGAGGGGCCACCCCGUGGGAGAGCAGCACGUGGGCUUGGAGAGGUGGGCACCAGUGCAGAUGGACGUCGGUGAAGGAGAAGGCGAGAGAGGCAGGAGGAAGACACCAGCACGGCCAAGGGAGACUCUGGGCGCGUCCCCGUGUUGGGGCCUUGGGGGAUGUGGUGGCUGCACUCCAGCCUGGGUGACAGAGCAAGACUCUGUCUUAAAAUAAAUUUUAAAAUUAAAGAAAA